AAGGAUCCCAAGGCCCAACUCCCCGAACCACUCAGGGUCCUGUGGACAGCUCACCUAGCUGCAAUGGCUACAGGCUCCCGGACGUCCCUGCUCCUGGCUUUUGGCCUGCUCUGCCUGCCCUGGCUUCAAGAGGGCAGUGCCUUCCCAACCAUUCCCUUAUCCAGGCUUUUUGACAACGCUAUGCUCCGCGCCCAUCGUCUGCACCAGCUGGCCUUUGACACCUACCAGGAGUUUGAAGAAGCCUAUAUCCCAAAGGAACAGAAGUAUUCAUUCCUGCAGAACCCCCAGACCUCCCUCUGUUUCUCAGAGUCUAUUCCGACACCCUCCAACAGGGAGGAAACACAACAGAAAUCCAACCUAGAGCUGCUCCGCAUCUCCCUGCUGCUCAUCCAGUCGUGGCUGGAGCCCGUGCAGUUCCUCAGGAGUGUCUUCGCCAACAGCCUGGUGUACGGCGCCUCUGACAGCAACGUCUAUGACCUCCUAAAGGACCUAGAGGAAGGCAUCCAAACGCUGAUGGGGAGGCUGGAAGAUGGCAGCCCCCGGACUGGGCAGAUCUUCAAGCAGACCUACAGCAAGUUCGACACAAACUCACACAACGAUGACGCACUACUCAAGAACUACGGGCUGCUCUACUGCUUCAGGAAGGACAUGGACAAGGUCGAGACAUUCCUGCGCAUCGUGCAGUGCCGCUCUGUGGAGGGCAGCUGUGGCUUCUAGCUGCCCGGGUGGCAUCCCUGUGACCCCUCCCCAGUGCCUCUCCUGGCCCUGGAAGUUGCCACUCCAGUGCCCACCAGCCUUGUCCUAAUAAAAUUAAGUUGCAUCA